GUAGAUGGAACUGGUAGUCAGCUGGAGAGCAGCAUGGAGGCGUCCUGGGGGAGCUUCAACGCUGAGCGGGGCUGGUAUGUCUCUGUCCAGCAGCCUGAAGAAGCGGAGGCCGAAGAGUUGAGUCCGUUGCUAAGCAACGAACUUCACAGACAGCGAUCCCCAGGUGUUUCAUUUGGUUUAUCAGUGUUUAAUUUGAUGAAUGCCAUCAUGGGAAGUGGCAUCCUUGGCUUAGCUUAUGUUUUGGCUAAUACCGGUGUCUUUGGAUUUAGCUUCUUGCUGCUGACAGUUGCUCUCCUGGCUUCUUACUCAGUCCAUCUUCUGCUUAGUAUGUGUAUUCAGACAGCUGUAACAUCUUAUGAAGAUCUUGGACUCUUUGCAUUUGGAUUACCUGGAAAGUUGGUGGUGGCAGGCACCAUAAUAAUUCAGAAUAUUGGAGCUAUGUCAUCUUAUCUUUUAAUUAUUAAAACAGAGCUUCCUGCUGCUAUUGCAGAAUUUUUGACUGGAGACUAUAGUAGAUAUUGGUAUCUUGAUGGACAAACACUACUAAUAAUCAUAUGUGUUGGCAUUGUGUUCCCUCUUGCACUUCUUCCCAAAAUAGGCUUUCUUGGCUACACAAGUAGUUUAUCAUUUUUCUUUAUGAUGUUCUUUGCUCUUGUGGUAAUAAUUAAAAAAUGGUCCAUCCCUUGUCCUCUGACAUUAAAUUAUGUAGAGAAAGGUUUCCAGAUUUCAAAUGUUACAGAUGAUUGUAAGCCAAAGCUCUUUCAUUUCUCCAAAGAGAGUGCUUAUGCCUUACCAACCAUGGCUUUUUCAUUUCUCUGCCAUACCUCAAUAUUGCCCAUAUACUGUGAACUUCAAAGUCCUUCAAAGAAAAGAAUGCAGAAUGUUACCAAUACAGCAAUUGCUUUAAGUUUUCUCAUUUAUUUUAUAUCUGCACUCUUUGGGUACCUCACUUUUUAUGACAAAGUGGAGUCAGAAUUACUAAAAGGUUAUAGUAAAUACUUAUCACAUGAUGUUGUUGUCAUGACUGUGAAGUUAUGCAUACUAUUUGCUGUGCUUUUGACAGUCCCUCUAAUCCACUUCCCUGCCAGAAAAGCUGUAACAAUGAUGUUUUUCUCCAAUUUUCCAUUCUCAUGGAUUCGCCAUUUUUUGAUCACUCUAGCACUCAAUAUUAUCAUCGUUUUACUUGCAAUAUAUGUUCCUGACAUUAGAAAUGUAUUUGGUGUAGUUGGUGCCAGUACAUCAACAUGUUUGAUUUUUAUAUUCCCAGGACUAUUUUAUCUUAAACUUAGCAGAGAGGAUUUUCUGUCAUGGAAAAAGCUUGGGGUUGGCGUGCAGUGGUGUGAUCUCAGCUCAUUGCAACCUCUGCCUCCCGGACUCAAGCAAUCCUCCCACCUCAGCCUCCAGAGUAGCUGAGACUACAGAACCUGCCUCCCAUCCCUACUUUACCCAUCCACCUCAGAGACUUCAUGGUACAGUGCAGUAUACUUGGUGAGUGUUGAUGGUUUAAGAGUGUGCCCUGAACAACGAAGGAUUUCUUUGAGGCUGAAAUCCUGUGGGAUCCAUGGAAUGGGAGUUUCACCUGUCUUUGGCUUCUGCUCCUUUCCCCAGCAUGUGUAGAGCUUCUAGAACAGUCCCCAGCAAGAGAGGAUCACUUGGUACACCUCUUUCUUAUCCUCACUGUCUCCAGUCUCUGCUGUAGGCCUGCUAGUGAUGAUCAGGAUACAGGUUUUAACAUGGCCAAGCUGUUAAUAACCUGAGAUUGGGCACCAUGAACAAUAAGCAUUAAAAGGCAAUAACAACAACAACAACAUAACCUGUUAAUUUUAUGCAGGCUUAAUUUUUUAAAGAACUAUUUCUUCCUAACUUGCUUUUACUCUUCUUCAUCUACUUUCUCAUACCUAUGACUGACAAUGAUAAGGACACCCACCCACUAUACACACCUAAUUCCAUCCCUCCAAAUUUGAUUUCGUGUUCUCUAGAGCUGGCGUGUUAUGUGACCUAUUGUGGGGAGAGGCUCAGCUGAGGGACUCUGUGAUGCCAAAUGGACAAAGGCACACUUUUUUCUCCAGGUCCCAGCCUGGUGAAAGUCAUAGCACCUGAGAAUUUGGAGCUGACUCUCUCCUUUGGAAAUUGUGCCUUCCAAAAAUAUAUCUUACACUGCCUGUACCUGCAUGCAAUAGGUUUUGGUUCUUACCAACUGCAGCUUCAGUCUGAACUUGAGUUCUACCCUCAUGGAUGCAAAUCAAAACAGCUCAGAAUCAAGUCUGGGAAGCAAGUCGAAGUGGUUUGAUUUGCAUGGGGAGCUUUUGUCUCUGCAUGAAGGCAGCCAAAUUCCCUAGGCUCCCCAGCCCUCCGGAAAUAUGCUUUACAGGACCCGGGGGCCCAGGCCCAGUCGGGUGGGUGUGAUUUGAAUGUUCUCUGCUACAGCUGCUGCACCGGGCCCUGGUCACUGCUGUUGGUUUCGCUCCAUUUUACUGCCUCAGAAUCCCCCUGUGCAUGUUAGUGGUUAAUACAGCAGCCAGGAGACGCCAGACAGCUCUCGGCACCUGGUUCAAAUUUAAGGCUCAUUUACACAUGAUGUCACACACGCAUUGUCAGCGCGAGGGAGGUCAGGAUGGUUCAUUUUGGGAAGGUUCACAUUGUUGAGUCUUUACAACACUCACUGCUAUUAAUGCUUUAACCAUCUGACUUGGAUUUCGGUUUUCUGGCAUGAGGUAAUCCCAGGCACUAGAUUUAUAUGCUGAAUGGGAAGCCAGCAAUGGUGGCUAAUCAUGCUGGUUUGCAGAUCUGCACCUCUGGAGCCUUGGGAUGGAAUUAGAGGGCCACAUGGCAAGUAGCAAAUCAUAGGCGUUUUGAGCAGGAGAGGAAUUAGCCAGACCUGGAAGCAGGGGCCAUAGAUGGGGUGUUGUCUGAGCCAGGAAGUUUGAUUGAAGAAUGGAAACCAAGGUAAAUUGGACAAGGAUCUGGGCCCAGAGACCACAGGAAUUAUUCUACUUUGACCAGUGCUUUGGGUCAUUGCUUGAACUGUCCUUUUGCUCAUCACUCAUAGAAAUCCCAGACCCAUCUUCCCAGGUCCAGCGUAAGUCUUUCAUGUUCCAUGAAGCCUUUCCUGACCACCCAUCCCACAGCAGGGGCUGAGGUGGUUAGAUCACCAGAGGUCAGAAGUUCGAGACCAGCCUGACCAACAUGGUGAAACCCCAUCUCUAAUAAAAAUACAAAAAUUAGCUAGGCGUAGUAGUGUGUGCCUGUAAUCCCAGCUACUCAGGAGGUGGAGGCAGGAGAAUCGCUUGAACCCGGGAGGCAGAGGUUGCAGUAAGCCAAUACCCGCCACUGCACUCCAGCCUGGGCGACAGAGCGAGACUCUGUCUCAAAAAAAAAUUUCUCUCCUGAAUCCCUAAGUACUUUUGUUACUGAGUACUUAAUUUGUGCGACUAGCUCAUUUUACCCUCACAAUUCCAAAGGGAAGGCUUUAUUAUUUCUCUUUUACAGAUGACAAGACAGGUUCAGAGAGGUUAAAUAAUGUAUCCAGUGUCAAACUUUUAAAAGUCAGGAUGGAAUCCUGAUUCCAAGCUUAGGUUCUGAACCACUGGGGUAGGCUGUGUAGUACUACAUUUUCUGUGGAACGUGGUAUCGGUAACAUGGGAGAGACAGGCUGUGCCUCAGGAAGAUGCCACAUGGGAGUGCACAGCAGUGCUGUAGUGCCUCGUGUUUAUGUGUAGUCCCAGGUGCCUGGCUGUAAACAACUGCAGGGCAGUGACCAUCACCUCUGCUUUUCUGCAUCCCCACACUUCCUAACACAGUGUCCCCCAAAGUGUGCAUCAAUGGAUGGAUGAAUAUUAGCACCCCCGCACCACCCUCACCUAAAACAUACUGAAAAGUUUGAGAUCUUUGGAUAACCACCCCAUCCCCUGCUGUUGUCUUCUGUCAUACGGCUGAAAUCGUAAAACUGGUCUGCCUGUCACAGCUCCAGUGAGCCUACUUACUCACUGGAAAUUCAGAGAAUGUCUUUAGUCCUGUUGACUGCUUUGAUUUUGUUUUUUAACUUGUACCAAGACCUGUUGCCAUGAUGGGUCUCUGCAAAUGGGCUUUCUUGUUCCAUGAGUCUCUGUUUUAGUCAAGUGAAGGGCACACUCCUUUUCAUUGGCCACCUCUUACUUUUCCUCCAAGAGGAGUACUCACUCCCAGAACCCUUUGCUGGGCUCUCAUGCCGAGCUUAGGUGCCCCUUCAGUGUGCUUCUGCAGCACUCAUUACCCCGUAGUAGCAUUGUAGUUUAAUUCCUGUUUGCUUGACUGAAGCAGAGACUCACCUGCAGACGCCUGUAGGUGCCUUCCACGUUGCUCAGAUGAACAGUAGAGAAGGGUCAGGCCUGCCCUAGGUUUCUACCCCUCUCCUCAAGGCCCUUUCUAGUCACCACGCCACAUCCUGCUCAUGACUGCAGGGAUCAUGCCUCUGGGCCUCUGUCCAUGCAGCUGCCUCUGCCUGCACUCCAGGACAGGGGCCUUCUCUGCUGUCCACUGGAGCCCUGUGGAAGGGACUCCUGACCCUAGCCUUAGGGAAGUCAUCUCUAAAGGCUGUUUUAUUACAGUGUUUCCUCAGAAUGACCCUAUAGACACAGUGUUUUCUCAGUGUCCUCUCACCUUUGAACAUAUCCGGGAAUAAUUGAAAAAACCAGGCAAUCAAAUGUGCCUCUCAUAAAUCACCAUCACUUCAGAGCAGAACUUAAGAGUUUGGUUUGCAAGCCACACCAAAUAGUUUGAGCUUGGCCCUCUACCAUUUCCUCCUGCUCUGAGCCCAGAGGUUCACCUAGUGGACUGUAGCAAUGGAUUCCCUUGCCCCUGGCUUCCUGUUGGGUUCAGCCAGAGAGCAGCACCAGUGGGAGCCUACAGAGGGAGGAAAGUGAGGUCAAGGUGUCUGCUGCCUCCUCCCUGCCUGCCAGGCCACUGUGGGUAGACUACACCUCAGGUGGCCCUCCCCAUGUGUAGCCAUGCUUGCCAGGUUCUGGGUUCUGGAAACCUCCACCUCCUCUUGCCCCUUCAGUCAUAGGGUGGUAGCCCCCUUCAUUGCUAUUAGCUGUUAUGCACUCAAUUGUGUUCCAACCCCAAAUUCGUAGGUUGAGGCCCCAAUCCCCAGGACCUCAGAAUGCAACUGUAUUUGGAGAUAGGGUCUUUAAAGAAGUAAUUAAAUUAAAAUGAGGCCAUUAAGCCCUAAUUCAAUGUGACUGGUGUUCUUGUAAGAAAAGGAAGAGAUACCAUGGAGAUGUGCACCCAGAGGAAAGGCCACGCAAGGACACAGCAAGAAGGCAACUGUUUACAAGCCAAGGGAAGAGGCCUCAGGAGAACCAAACGUGUCCACACCUUGAUCUUGCACUUCCCAACCUCCAGAACUGUGAGCAAAUAAAUGAUGUUGUUUAAUCACCCA